GGCAGAAGCCGCACUGGCUGGUGCUGGGUGAGCUCCACCGCUGCCCGGGCUGCGAGCCUGACGGCUGUGUGUCGGGAAUGACGAGACCCAGGCUUGCAAAGACUUGCACGGCAACUGGAAUUUAUGACAAAUAGCUCACUGCAGCUAAACUUUGAUACAGUGUACAGUAGAACCGCCUGUUACACACAGGAGGGAGACGCGUCCUUCGUCACCAUGCAAAGCCAGCCUUAACACAACAUAGGAAAAUGUGGCAGGUCUCUAAUUACGGACUGAGAACAAGCAGAAGAGGAGUGACACUGCAGAUUCCGAGGCACUGCAGUGGGAUGUUGGCUCAGCAAGUGGCUGUGAUGUACGGGAUAGGCAUGGAACAGGAUUCCAGCUGUUCCAUGCAAAUAGGAUAAAAGAAUGGUAAAGAGGAUUCCUUUUUUUUUCCCUCCUCAAAACGUUACCAGCAAAGUACAUUCACAGAGCCUUUUUAAGGUGCCUUUUGCCAGCUUUUGAACUGAACUUGUACCAGUAUCUCAAGCCCUGAAUUGUAAGAAGAGCUGAGAGUUCUGGAACUCAUUUUUAAAAAGUAGAUCUACGAAGAUUCUAGGACGUCCGUUUCUGUUACUGGCUCCUUCUUGUGCUUGGAUGCAGCUCCCUAGCAUGCACCAGGCUUUAGCGUCAGUGCUACCUGGGGGAUGGAGCCAGUCCAGAAAGGGCCAGUCACAUCCAUCUCAUAGCUCACCCUGUCACAGAAGAAAAGAGAGCAUGUUUCCUUUCUCCACUGUCAGAGGUCUCUUCUUUCUGCAUAGCAGUUUGCAUCUUCAGAGCAACGUUGAGGAUGCUGAGUCAGGUUUAAAGGAUGUUUGGUCAGAAAAAACACAAGCAUGGUAUGUUGCAAAUACAGUUCCAUCAUGUCCUCACACCCAUCAAUUCUACCCAUCCUUAAGGACCUAUUCCAAAUCUCUGUCCCCUGGAAAGUUCUCCCUAAUCACCCCAACAGGAGGUCAUUUCUAAAUCCUUGAAACUCCCAUUAUAGAGUUAAGUUUCUAUUCAUUCAUGUGUUUUCUUGCUAUAGCUCUUCUAAGGGUGUUUUGAACAGCAAUGUGUAUAUUUCAUGAUGCUUUAUAUUUUCACACAUGUAUAUCUUAUAUUCCCACCUAAAUUGUAAUCUCAUUGAAGGCAGAGAUCAAGAUUUAUGCUUUUUUCUGCUGUCUACAUCUCCUAGCAGUUCCCUACACAUGGAACCCUUUCAAUAAAUAGUUGAAUAGGAAGAGGGGCAGUUUAAAAAGCAGGAUUUUUUUUUUUUUUUUUUUUUUUUUUUUUUUUUUUUUGGUCAUAGAGAGUUAGAAUGAUCUGGUUUUGCUAAUUUUAAGAAUCUUCACAGGGUAUAUUCAGGCUAAGGUGGACCUCAGGAGUCAUGCAUGCCACUCUAGAAGUUGUGAUGGUUCUUACCCUGAGACAGUGUCACAGCCAGGAAGCUGCCUUACCCUGCUUGUAAAGAACUGUUGCCGUAAAGGACAAAUGAGCAUGUGGACAUUGAUCACGGUUUACUUGAAUUAUAUUGGACAAGCCAUCCUUAAGUUAUGAGGAGUAUGCCGAAUUCGGGAAGUUUAGGUGAAAGUCACUUUUUUGACUCCUACAGGACAUUUUCCUUAGAAGAAAGAGCCAGAAUGGUUACUAAUAAUUCGGAUCAUAUCAGAAAUUAUUUAACUCCUGGUGUCACUGAUUUUUAAUACUAAGAGUACUUAUUUAAGUCCUGAGUUUCCUUUCCCUUUCUUAGGUAAUGGAUUGGCCCAACCUAAGUUUUGAAAUAGGUCAACAUCCUUUGAUAUCCUUGUAAUUCUCUAUCCACACUAUUUCCCAUCUCCUAGUGCCUUUUUCUCUCCAAAGUCCCUAGUGUAAUGCAUGUUUGCACUCCCAGCCUGGUGAUGCAUCCCAAAUGCUAUGUGUUCUAUAUAUCUGAUUAAAGUAAUCUUAUUAAACUACUUCAUACUAGUAUAAGGAAGACCUCUGCACUCUUAGCCUUCCCAAAGAUAUUUUAGUUUUUUAAAAAGGCUUAUUUUUAGGUACAAACAAAUUUUCCAUUGGUAGAAAUUCAAACACUGUAAAUGAGUAAAUUGGAUAAAUCUAGAUGGGCUUGAGGAAGAAUUUUUUUUUUUUUUUGACGGAGUCUUUCCUUGUUUCCCAGGCUGGAGUGCAAUGGCACGGUCUUGGCUCACUGCAACCUCCGCCUCCUGGGUUCAAGUGAUUCUCCCGCCUCAGCCACCCGAGUAGCUGGGAUUACAGGCAUCUGCCACCACGCCUGGCUAAUUUUUUGUGUUUUUCGUAGUGAUGGGGUUUCUCCAUGUUGGCCAGGCUGGUCUUGAACUCCUGACCUGAUCCACCCACCUCGACCUCCCAAAGUGCUGGGAUUACAAGCAUGAGCCACCGCGCCCGGCCAGGGAAGAUAUUUUUAAUACUAGCUACUAUUUAUUAAACAUGUAUUAGGUCUCAGGGACAGGGUAAGCACUCAACAUCCAUUAUCUCAUUUAAUCCCCUCAGUGAGUCUACAAGGUAAACAUCAUUAUGUAUACUUCACAAAAGAAAAAAUUGAAACUCAAAAAAUUAAAUAAUUUGCCCCAAAUCACACAACCAGUGAGGAGCAGAACUGGGCUCUGAACCUAAAGUUUUGACUACAAAGCCCAUGGCUUUUAACACCAUCUUGUAAUGCUGAAUUGAAGAGAGAAAAGUUACUUAAUUGUACAGCGACUUAGACGUUUCCUCUGUGUAUCUGAUCUGAUCCCCUAUCCUUUCUUUCAUGCCUCUGAAUUCUGACAUAGUCCUUUCAUAAUGACCUCCAUGGCAGUUGGAAGGGGUAGAAGCGUGUUCGGUUUUAGGGGGGUUGGUUGGUAGCAGUCAAUCGGUACAAUUUUGUUGUAAUUUGGGAACUGUCAACCUGUCCAUAUUUGUAGUUUAUUUAAUUAGGCCUUCCUGUCCUAUUACAAUUGUAUUUUACAGAAAUCAGUCCCACUACAGUUGUCAUCCCUAAACUGAUGAAGCAGAGAAUACAAAGACUGAGAAAUAGCUCUGGUGAUUCCAACUUAAAAAGAGGGAAAGUGAAUGUGUGACCUAGAGUUGUUAGAUGAUUUAUUAAGCUGAAGUUGGGAAAUAUCAUCAGUGGAAACUGGAGCAUCUAAUGUCUAGUGUUAGGCCAGGUUAUGCUGCAGAAUGAACAUGAAGGAGAAGUACAGGGUGGCUUAAAAUAGGAAUUUAUGUUCUUUCUUAUGUGAUGCACUUAAGGAAAAGGAAGACGUCAUGUUCCUCAGGUGCUCUUGUUGGUCAGGUGCUUUACAGAAUUUCAGGACAUCUGGGAGAUCUUACUAAUUGUUAUCAUCUAGGACUGGUAUUUCAUCAUAACUUUAUCCUUGUUGGUAAGUGGCUUUACCUUCAUUCUGGUUGAAGGACUGGAGCACAAGUGGCAGCUGGUGUUGGAAAACAUCUUGUAAGGUAGCAGGGCCUUGCCUCUUCUUGUUUAUGUACGUAGGACCUUUUGAUUCUACAAGCAUUUGAGGACCUGCCGUGUGAAAGCAUUCGGCUAGGUUUUAUUCCAUGUGCCUAGCACGUACCACCCUGGACCUAGCUGAUGGGUUAUAGUGUGGAGCCUUAGCAAAGGCGUUAAUUACGAAAUUAACCUGAUUGGUCCCAGGGCUCAUAUUCCAUCCUACCUUUUCUGCUAUGCAUCUAUUGCAAAUAGCUAAAUGGUCCAACAGAAGUGUUAGUUGUUCCUAUCAGAGACGUCAGGAAUCACCUCUGGCGGUGGGGAAGGUGGCUCUUGGCCAGGGCGCUCUCACCCACCCCUGCCCACGAGGAUGGCCCCUUUCUGCCCGAUGCUCUACCCUUUCUGCCUUAUCUGUCUCUAUUUAUUCUGUGAUAAGCUUUUACCUGUAGUCAAAUCUCAGUAACAAGAGCAAUAGCUAAUGUGACUAACGAAAGGUUGCGGACUGGGAGGAUCAUGAGCUUCUUCUGUAGACCAAUGAGCCAAUUAAUUCGUUACUUCACAUAGUGGCAUUAGACAGACUGGUCAGCACAAAGGCCCGGGUGACGUGGGGGAUGUUAACUCAUUCUUUUGGGUGCCCUUGGCCACCGUGUUACUCUCGUUUAACUUUAUUCCCAUUAGAAGUUUCUUAGUAAGUAAUAGCUAAUGGACACCAGUAUUUCAGUAUGAUUAAUGAGUGUCUUCUGUUUACGCUCUCUUGAUUAAAAUGAUUUACUCAAAUAAUAGCUUAGGAAUUGGACCUGCUUUAAGAUACCCAUUAAGUGUUGAAGUAAAGCAUUAGGAAACAUUUUUAAAGUUGUUAUAGAAUCUCUAAAUAUUCUAAAAUUCCUUUUUUAUGCUGUUUCCUUCAGUUGACUAUUGCCAUCGGGCUCAGCCUUCAACUUUUGAAAUCAGUGGCAUUUGAAACAAACCUACAGUAAACUAGUAAAAGUGCCUUUUCAUUGCCAGUUUUCUUCUGAAUGUCAAAUACAAACAUUCGAAAGUCAAGAAUAGUCAUCUGGUUUCAAAGGAAAGCUGCUUAAAACGCAGGAGCAUGUGAGGUAAUGGGAGCCGUCUGCUCUGCCCCCACCAGAUGGGUGCUGUGGUCUUCAAGAGAGCGCAUAGGAAAGAAGUAUGUGGGUUUUUUUAGAACAGCUUUUUAAAAAAUACUGUAGUAGGCCUUCUGUUAAAAGAGCCAAACAGCAUUAAUACAUAAAAUUGGGGUUAAUAAAUUGAAUUAAAUUGUAAAACACAAGAUUUGUCUGAGGCGCUGCAUCCGAGAAGUUGUUCACUUGACUGUAACCCCAGAAAGCGGGUGAUUUCCCCAAGCCCAAGGGCAUUUAAGAUAAAACUUGGCGAAAGAAUCGUUUUCUGAAGAGUGUGCGGAGAGGAAUAGAGUUGUGUUGUCCCCAUGCCCAUAGUGCAUUUUAUAGACAUGUUUGACUAUUUUUAUGAGGAAUCACGGUAUCUACUACUUGUGGUAAUUUUAUGGCAUCCGUGAUUUUAACUUGCGUGUUAAUUUUGGCGGUGCAGAGAACAAAAGGGGCACACAUUAGUCCUGAGGAACAAAGCUGAGCAAGACUUUGAAUUUAGAAAGAGAAAAUGAUGAAGCCUUUAUUGUAAGGGAAGAAAAAAUUAUUAGCCAGUAUAUGGAGCCAUUUCUUUGAAAAUUAAAGCCCAACUUUUUCAGUUCAGAUGAGUGUUAAAAUAGUGUCCCCAGCGUGAUGGAAGCAGAGCUAGACACCCGUGCCAUAUGAUGCUUUUAUGCCAGAAUUCUGCUGCAUUCAUAUAGGAUCACAGGAUUUAGGAGGCUGAAGGAAUCUUUGAAAUCAUUUCAUCCAAACUCUCAUUUUACAGAUGAGGAAACGGGCGCAGAGCGGAUAAUUGUAUUUUGUUUUAAGAGACUGGGUACUUAUCAAAAUAUCUCUUGAAUGCUUUUUUUAUAUUGGGAAUUUCUCAAUUAUAAACUAGUACAGUUUCAGAACCACAUUCUUAAGUGGGUUGUUUUGGUACAAGAAUUUCAUUAAUGUCAAAGAUAACUCUUCAACCCAGAGAAUAGAUUACAUUAACACUUGCAAUGAAAAACAGUACCUUAAAAGGAAAACAGGAUAAUUCAUAUGGAAUGUUGGUGCUUGAAAAAAAAAUUAUUUAAAGAAAGCUAAGAUAGAGGAUGGAGGCUGGUACUUUCCAGGCUGUUUACUGUGAUGCAGUUUGCCUGGGGAAAUUCUGGCUUUCCUUUUCUUACACAGUUGUAUGAGGAUGGGUACUUUAAGAUGAAAUGACAUAGUUUUAUGUUGGCUUUUGUAGCAGGUAUCUUUUGGAAAGCUACGGAUGUCACCCAGGAAGGAGCAGGUGUAAGCUGUUGUGAAAGUCAUAUCCCAGGAGCGGUGCUGGUCUCCUGCGUGUGCACAGGCUGAGAAGUUCCUGGAACCUCAAUUAAUGACUGCAAAAAGUGAAAAUGCCACUUAUAAAGGACAGGGCUUUAUUUUAGUCUUUUUUUUUUUUUUUUUUUUUUUUUUUUUUUUGCACAAAUAGAACCGAGAUAAGAACAGUUUUGGAACUUGAGUGCUUAAAGGUAUUUGAUGUAAAAUAGGCAUUCAGAUAUUUCUUGAAAGGAUGAAUUAUGUGAGAGAGAGUUUUUUUUAAAAUAACUCCAACUAAAGUAAUGGGCCAGAAGUUGGAAGGGGAAAAUAGAUAGAGGGAUUUAAAUAGUGAAAAUGGAUGCGCUUGAUAAAGCUAUUUCCUGAGGUAGGGGUGACUAGCUGUAGACAAUCCAAGAGCAGGUUGGCGUCUGCAGGACAUCUGCCUGUUGUCCGUUGUGCGAGUGAUUUUAGGAAUCACCAGCUCUUUCUCCAGAGUUGCACAAGAGUGAUUUUCUCAUGCAAGCAUAUCAUGUGAUUUGUCUGUAUGAAAACAGGGGCAGUGCCUCGUCACCGUCAAGAAUAAGAUCUAAGCCUUCUUGUCAACCAGGAUCUGGCCCCUUUUUUCUCUGUAUCUCACCACCAGCCUGCCCCAGGGGAGCCUGAACCUGCCGCAGCUCCCCAGUCUCAGCUCCCCGGGCUGCCUGGGCUCAGCAUGCUGCACCCCCGUGCUGGCUGGGCUGUUCCGCCUCUCCUGGAGGGGGUCCGUCUUCCAUGCCCCUCAUCAUCCACCCGGCUACUCUUUCUCUUCAUGCCAGUCAGCCGACAAUGACCUCACAUGAAAGCAGUGUCCACAUUUUCACUCAUGCAUUUUAAAUGUUAAAUACUCUUAAAACAGAAGUUUACUUACAAUUGUAAUAUUUUCAUGUCUUUUCACAUUUUAAGCUCGCUUAAAAAUCUAUGGAAUGCUUCCUCUGUCCAAGGCACUGAGUUUGGUUUUAUCUGAAAUAGCCUAGAUUUGACAAAAGUCCUCUGAGGACUGUACUUAAAUGGAUGUUUGUAAGAAAAUAAAGCUGAACUAAAAUCUAUCUACUCCUUUUUUAGAACAAUAGGACAGAAUUAUAGCAGUUUAGAAAGAAUUUUUUAGCUGACAAAGUGCCAAUGUGCUUUAAGAUGAGUUGUCGUUAUGAAUGUGUUCUGAACUAAUUCUGACGAUGGAAAAAUCCAUCCUAUAAAUUAUAGACAAGUAAAUUAUAAUCCACAUUUCAUGCAAAAUAUGGUAGUUUCUGUAGAUAAUGUAGAUUAUCGUGACCAACAAUAUUUUAGCAGUACCUACAUUCUCCUUUUUUCUUCUUUGAAUAAAUAAAUGUGGUCCGGUAGUUGGAAGAAUUUUCUAGUAGCAUAUCUUAAAAAUGACUAGUUGGCUCGUUAAGCAGGUUUAUAUAAGAUCCACAGAAGAUUAUGGUAAACUUGAAUAAUGUUUAUGUUGUGUUGAGAGAUACCUGUGAUUCCUUUAAUACAGAUCUUAAAUGCAUGUUCUAAACUUCACUUAAUAUAUAAUUAUUCUUUUAAAAAAUUUACUCAUUUUUAUUAAUUUUUAAUUUCUUAUUGCUAUAUAAUAGUUGUGUUAUAAAGUUAUUUUUCUAUAGUAACUGCUGUGUUUGGAGGCCUAUUUCUCAUGCAGUUAAUUGGGGGAGUCUUAGAAAUUGCAUGGGUAAACUUAUUUGUUCUCUUUUUGUUUGCUAUUAUUUAGCAAAAAUAUUAAUAAAAUUACAGUCCUUUAAGAUGACUAAGAAAUUCCUUAGAUUAUCAUGUUAAAAAUGGAUAUUCAUUCAUUCAACAAAUAUUUGUUGGGUAAGCACUGCAUCAUUCUAGGUGCUGGGAAUGUGGCAUUCACGUUGCCUUCUGUCAUGGAGCUUACAUUCAAGUGGGUGAGACAGACAGUAAACCAGUGAACCAAACGCACAUGCACACAUGCAGGGAGAGAAGACAGUAAACUCGGCUGUGAUGGAAUGGCAGUAGACCAGACAGUCAGGUUAGGGCUUUCUGAUGAGGUGCCAUUUGAAUUGAGACCUAAAGCAUGAAAAGCCAGUCUUGAAAGGUCGACCCAAGGAGCAUCCCAGGCCAAGGGCACAAAAAAUACAAAGGCCCUGAGUUGAGGAAAUGCCUGACAUGUUCAAAGAACAGAGGAGGUCGUGAGUGGCAAGUAAGGAUGGAGGUGGGAGUGGUCCUAGCAUAGGGUGGACAGGCUCAGGCCACGUGGGCCCGUGUAGGCCUACCAAGGAGUUCAGCUUCUCUUCUAAGUGCAGUAGGCAGUCCCUGGAGGAUUUUAUGCAGGGAAGUGGUGUGUUUUUUGUUUUCCUAAGAGGACCUUGCCUGCUCUGUGGAGAGGGGAGUGUUGGAGGCAGGAGGGAAGGCUGAACAUCAUCAAGUUCUUAUGAAGGACCAGGUGAGAGAUGAUGGCAGUUUAAGGGAGCUCCAGGGAUAGAAUCCAGGGGACAGGCCAGGAAGCAUUUGGGUGUAGACAGGAUUGCUGAUGGGAUUGGGGAUGGGAAAGGAGUUGAAAGUAAUAUAUCUUAGUGCAGCACAAAAAUGAGAUGAGGUGGAGACAGUUACUUAGAACAUCCAAAUUCCAUUUUGUUCUACAUUCUGAGUUAAAAGUUAUUGCCCAUAUUCAUUAUUAUAGUGAAACUGAGCUUUUCCAAAGUAAAUGCCAUUCAGACACACUUAAAGCAUGCUGCCUCUUGGAGUUGGCUGCAAUGAAUGAAAAGAAAUUAACUGAGAAUAUGGCAGUGAAACCAAACAAAUUGUUUCAGCUAAACCCAUAAGGACAAGCAUGACCUAAACCAAAGCAGUUAAUUAAUUUUGCUAAUAGUCAUUUCUUUUUUACAGAGAGUUCGAGUUUCCUCUUAUGACCUAUACAAAAAUCUGGAAAUAGUCCGGCCUGCAUUUUGGGGAUCAUAUUUAGUAUUUUUGUAUCUUUCAUCUUCUGAGAUGUUCUUAGUUAUAUAAUAGGCACACGUUGGAAGGUAUUAACUUCUCAAGUGAUACCCAAGUCCAGAGGUUCUGGAAUCUGCAUUGAUCCUGUCCCUCUUUGCCAGCUGAUCCCAUCUUCCUUUUCAUCUGACUUUAAAAAUCAUCCCAGGUGACUUUCAGGUCCAUAUGGCUAACUUAGCACCUCUGUAAGAAAGCCGGCCUCAGUGCCCCUGUCCUAUCCAGUGGAGGUGGAGUGAGAGAGAAGGAACUACAGGCCGGUGUCUCAGACUGUCUGUGCCUGAGCUGUAGGGCCUGCGGUACGGAGGGCAGAGUCAAACAGGUGAACUUCCCAACUCCCACCUCUGCUGCAGCUUGCAUCAGCACUCAGCCAAUCUUCACACAUUUCUUAUGUGUUUAUUGAUUUAGAGACAGGGUCUCGCUCUGUUGCCCAGGCUGGAGUGCAGUGGCGCAAUCUCAGCUCACCGUAGCCUUGACCUCCCAGGCUCAAGCGAUCUUCCCAGCUCAGCCUCCCAAGCAGCUGAGACCACAGGCGCGUGCCAGCAUGCCUGGCUAAUUUUUGUAUUUUUUGUAGAGAUGGGGUCUCAUCAUGUUGCCCAGGCUGGUCUCAAACUCCUGGGCUAAAACAAUCUGCCUGCCUUGACCUCUAGAACUGUUGGGAUUAUAGGUGUGAGCCACCAUGCCCAACCCACAUUAGGUUUUAGAGUAAGACUUCAUUUGGGCUGGGCAUGGUGGCUCACACCUGUAAUUCCAGCGCUUUAAGAGGUGGCCGGACUGUAGUCCUAGCUAUUUGGAAGCCUGAGGUAGGAGGAUCUCUUGAGUUCAAGGUUGCAGUGAGCUAUGAUUGUGCCAUUUCACUCUAGCCUGAGCCACAGAGCCAGACCCUGUCUCAAAAAAGCAAACAAACAAAAAAACAAAAACAAAUGAACAAACAAAAAAACCCAGCUUUUUUUGUAGGAAAAAAAAGGAUAUGACAAAUCUUUUCUUUAAGAUUUAAAUACAUUGUUCUAGGCCGUUGGAAACUUACCCACUGAGGUGGUCCCAGCCCACGUCAUUCUAUCAUUCUGUCAUUUUUGAGUUACCAAUACGAACUGAGCUUCACCAGCCAAUGAAUGAAACUCACAUCCCCCAAAAUGGCCCCAAGUUCACACUCGGUCUCGCCUGCUACUGCCCCACAAAAUAUUACAAGAAUUUUUCUGAGGGUGUCUCUUUAUGAUGCCUAUGACCCAUAGGCCCCAGACAUUUGUGGCUUCUAAGCUAGGUCAGUUCCUGGCUUCUGCUGAUUUUUCUCCCUUCCUCCUUUUCUGGAUGUGGGUACUCCUGUCUCCCUCUGGCCACUGGGACAACGUCUUAUCCUCCUCAUAUCCAUCUUGCAGAGAGUGGAGCUACAGUAGAGCUGAUGGGAGCCCCAUGUGGUCCAGGGAAAGGGGGGCGUUGAACUGAGCUGGGUUUGGGAAGGGGGUGAGGCCUGAGCCUUGGGCACUGGAGUCCUGCUGCUUCCUCCGAGGCACCUGUUGGACUCUCCCCGUACGUGCUGAUCUUUGUCCCAGGCCCUGCUGCCUGAUUUCAUCGAGCAAACCAUUUCUCUCCUAGCCCAUCAAAGCAGCAAGUUUUUCCCCAUAGGGACUCUGCACUCCUCCUGCAAACUAGGAACUGUGGCUGGGCAUGGCUUUAAGUGCCUGACAGUGAGGAGGUUGGUCCACCUCAGAGCAGCCAGACACCUUGUCGGGGAGGGUGUUGCUUAAUGCUACAGGCCGACCUGAGUCUCGGUUUUGGUCAACCAUGGUAGCUUAUUACAAGCAUGCUUCAGAAACAAAAAAGGCUAGAUUAUGGAAGUACAUUUAGGAAAUCAGAUUAGAAACUUAACAGACCCUGUGAGCCCUUCUAUGUUCUACUGUGUUGAUAGUUUGCAUCCUCCUCGUGUAGGACAUCUUUUCAAAUGCAACCUUGGAGAACCCCAGGUAUAAAACAGGUGGCACCCAGGUGUCAGGAGCGAACUUUCCUGCCCUCCCAGCCUCUGCUUCUACUGGGGGCACCUCCAUCCCAGAAAUAUUCCAAGAAAUUCUAGGGAUCCUUGGAGCAUCACUUGAAAAUCACUGACUGCACUGUGGUAUAAAGACUUGAGAAAUGAAGACAGAUAUUUGCAUUGUAGGUUGACAUCUCAAGAGUCACCGUCCAUCACCCCUCCGAUGCAGGGUCUUCAGCCUCUCCUGCCUCCACUGGCCCUUUUAGUGUGCAGGAGGCCACAUUCUCUGAGGGAAUUGUAAUCUGCCUUCUCCCACUCCUCCCAGCCAUCAUCCCCACGGCCACCACAGUCAUCUUUCUGAAAUCCACACCUGCCUUCAGCCUUCCAUGGCUCACCACCCCUCAUAGAAUGCAGAGCUUGGACACUCAGCUCUUUAUUCAUGGUCGUCCCUACCUACCUGUCCCCCUUCGCUUCUGUGCCCCAGAAAACAUCUGCUUAUAGGUCCCAGCCCCGCAGGGACACACCUACUCUUGAACACUGGGUUCAGAUUACACUUCCUUGGUGGAACCUUGGAAAUUCCUGCUUCUGAGCCCCACCCUCGCCUCCCAGAGGUGUUAUCCUUCCUCGACUCUCAGCACCCAGGUGUUGUUCUGUUCUCUUGUGUGCCUGCCACGCAGCAUUGCGAACUUCGUUCGAUCUACUUGUCUGUCUUCUCCACUUAAAUAGAAACUGAGGGCAGAGAUGUUUGGGGAGAGGCGCGCACUCUGUCUCUGCAGCUCCCGUUCCCCCAGCAGACACGUAAACGCGUUCAAUGUGUGAAUGAAUGAAUCAUCAAGUUACACAAAUGCAAUUUGUCGGGAUAUGAAUGGCAGUUAUUAAAUAAAUCAGCUCCAAGUUAAUAAAAACGGAAAUAAAAGCCUGUUGUUGCAAGACUUUCAGUACUAGGACUAUUUAAAUGAGAUCUCGGAUGUUAAAGGGAAGUUUUAUUUGUUGAGGCAGUAGGAGCUUCCACUGCGUGUGGAAGUCUUUCCACCUGAGUGGAAUUGGCUGUGGCUUCUGUGUUCAGAGUGGAAUUGGCAAGCAGCUGCUAUGUUCGGAGCUGACUGUGUUCGUCAGACCAGGGCCAGAUGGACGCGUGAAGGCGUGUGUCUGACAGAUGACCGGGUCUUUUAAUGAACCACUCACUUGAAAAUUGUCUUUCUGCAGGUGAUGUAUCACCCAUCAGUAUGUCUCCCAUCAGUCAGUCUCAGUUUAUUCCACUCGGGGAGAUCCUCUGCUUGGCCAUCUCAGCAAUGAACUCGGCAAGAAAGCCUGUCACCCAAGAAGCACUGAUGGAGCACCUGACCACGUGCUUCCCAGGUGUUCCAACGCCAAGCCAAGAAAUUCUGCGGCACACGCUGAACACGCUGGUACGGGAGAGGAAGAUCUACCCAACUCCAGAUGGCUACUUCAUCGUGACCCCACAGACUUAUUUCAUAACUCCUUCCCUCAUAAGAACUAACAGUAAAUGGUACCAUUUGGACGAGAGGAUACCUGACCGGUCUCAGUGCACCUCUCCGCAACCCGGGACCAUCACGCCCUCUGCCUCAGGCUGUGUCAGGGAAAGGACAUUGCCCCGAAACCACUGCGACUCUUGCCACUGCUGCAGAGAAGACGUGCACAGCACGCAUGCACCCACCCUGCAAAGGAAGUCUGCCAAGGACUGCAAAGACCCUUACUGUCCCCCUUCUCUGUGCCAGGUGCCACCCACUGAAAAGAGCAAAAGUACUGUAAAUUUUUCCUAUAAGACAGAAACUCUCUCAAAACCUAAAGAUAGUGAAAAGCAGUCAAAAAAAUUCGGGCUAAAGUUAUUCCGGUUAAGUUUUAAAAAAGACAAGACCAAACAGCUGGCCAAUUUUUCUGCCCAGUUUCCUCCUGAAGAGUGGCCCCUGCGAGACGAGGACACGCCAGCUACGAUCCCUCGGGAAGUAGAGAUGGAAAUCAUUAGGCGCAUUAACCCAGACCUGACCGUGGAAAAUGUCAUGCGGCACACCGCGCUCAUGAAGAAACUGGAAGAAGAAAAGGCCCAGAGGAGUAAAGCCGGGUCCUCUGCCCAUCACAGCGGAAGGAGUAAAAAGAGUAGGACUCAUCGGAAGUCCCAUGGAAAGUCUCGGUCUCACAGCAAGACACGGGUGUCUAAAGGAGACCCUUCCGACGGUUCACAUCUGGAUAUCCCAGCUGAAAGAGAGUAUGACUUUUGUGAUCCUCUUACCAGGGUGCCCAGGGAGGGCUGCUUCAUCAUUGAACACAAAGGAGAUAACUUCAUCAUGCACAGCAACACAAACGUGCUCGAGUCCCACUUCCCCAUGACACCAGAAUGGGAUGUGUCUGGUGAAUUGGCUAAAAGGAGAACUGAGAUGCCUUUUCCUGAACCUUCUAGGGGAAGCUCCCACUCAAAAGUGCACCGAAGCCACAGCCAUACACAGGACCGGAGGUCCAGGAAUGAGAGAUCCAACAAAGCCAAGGAGAGAUCCAGGUCGAUGGAUAACUCCAAAGGCCCUCUGGGUGCUUCUUCUCUAGGGACGCCGGAAGACCUUGCUGAAGGCUGCAGCCAAGACGACCAGACCCCCAGCCAAUCCUACAUUGACGACAGUACUUUAAGGCCUGCACAGACCGUUAGUCUCCAAAGGGCUCACAUUUCGUCCACAAGCUAUAAAGAGGUGUGUAUUCCAGAGAUAGUCAGUGGCAGCAAGGAACCGUCCAGCGCUUGCAGCCUUUUGGAGCCAGGAAAACCACCCGAGAGUUUGCCAUCCUAUGGCGAACUCAACUCUUGUCCAACAAAAACAGCCACAGAUGACUAUUUCCAGUGCAACACCUCUAGUGAGACGGUGCUCACGGCACCAUCACCUCUGGGAAAGAAUAAGGAGGACCAUGACACUCUGACUUUGGCAGAAGGGGUGAAAAAGCUCUCCCCUUCUGAUAGGCAGGUCCCCCACUCCUCCAGGGAGCCUGUGGGGCACAAGGAGGAGUCACCAAAAGGGCCGGGUGGGGGCCCCGCUGCUUCGGGAGGAGUGGCUGAAGGGAUCGCCAACGGACGCCUCGUCCAGCACCAUGGUGCCGAGCCCAGCAGCUUGGACAAGAGGAAAGAGAUAUUUAGCAAAGACACACUGUUCAAACCUCUUCACAGCACCUUGUCUGUAAACAGCUAUCACAAGUCGAGCCUGUCCCUCCUCAAAUCUCACCCGAAGACACCUGCUGACACAUUGCCAGGCCGAUGUGAGAAACUGGAACCGUCCCUGGGGACCUCGGCGGCACAAGCCAUGCCUGCUUCCCAGCGUCAGCAGGAGUCAGGAGGGAACCAGGAAGCCUCUUUUGACUAUUACAACGUCUCUGAUGAUGACGACUCUGAGGAAGGGGCAAACAAGAACACAGAGGAGGAGAAAAAUAGAGAGGACGUAGGCACCAUGCAGUGGCUCCUCGAGCGGGAGAAGGAAAGAGACUUGCAGAGGAAAUUUGAAAAGAACCUCACCCUUCUUGCUCCAAAAGAAACCGACAGCAGCAGCAACCAGAGAGCCACCCAUUCAGCCCGGCUCGACAGCAUGGACAGCAGCAGCAUCACAGUGGACAGUGGAUUCAACUCCCCACGUACUCGGGAGAGCCUGGCUUCCAACACAUCAAGCAUUGUUGAAAGUAACCGUCGUCAGAACCCCGCUUUGAGCCCGGCCCAUGGUGGAGCUGGUCCAGCCUUCAACUUCCGAGCGAGCGCGGAGCCCCCGACAAAUGAAGCUGAGAAGCUACAGAAACCUUCCAACUGCUUGCAAGCUUCUGUUACUAGCGUGUGAUUGUCCUUCUGCCUCAGAUCUUCUGUCUCAUUCGAUACAGCAAAGUUUACGACACUGGGACUGAUGUUUACAUCUUUGGAAAGACAAGCAUCUCAACCACAGUUUUUGUGUUUACUUAAACUGUGCUGCUAAGUAGGGCUAGGGCAAAAAAACAAAAAAUCUUUAUUUCAGAGUAUUGCUUUUCACAUUUAUGGCUCUGUAGCAACUGAGUAACAGUAGGGGUGAUAUGUAUACUUUUGCUUCACUAAUUGUAUCUGAGCACACAUAGGAAAGUCUAGACACUGUAAGUGUAAUACGCAUUUUCAAUGUCAUGCAGUUGCCAAUUCCAUUUUAAAAUGCCACAGAUGCGUGUUGCUCCCAGUCUGUGGUUAAACGGUGCCACAGAACUGAUCCUUGACACUUCCAAAAAAAAAAAAACAAAACAAAACAAAAAAAAUUUAAAAAAAAAAAACAAAAAACAAAACUAAGCUACCACGAAAUGUCAAAUGCAAGGGUCCACCUUGAGGGAAAUAGAUGCCAAACUAACUAGAAGGGACCCCGGCCCUUUGUGUGUGAAUUGUUUAUGCACCAGUCAUUUUUCACUGUGAGUUUUCGUGACACUAUUUUGCAGGAGCCCAUGGAAGUGUGUGAGAAGGGGUCGCAAUGGAGAUCACUGGGAGUGAAUGUUUUCAGGGUUUUGUUUUGAAGUGUCACAGAUGCUUGUCUGAUUUUUUUAACCUUCCGUGAUCACAAACAGGAAUAUAGGCCUUUGAAUCUGAAGUGGACAAAGGAAAGCAAUUUCCAGUCUGGCUGGGGCACAGCAUUAGGUGAUUGAAAAGGUGAUGUGGACUUGUAAAAGGUGUUACUCAAAUAUUGAAGGAAGAGAAUUUCCUCCUUGUGAUACUUAGGAUGACCCUAUCUUACUCUAAUAGAUACAAUAAUUAGUUUGUUUAAAAGCAAAAUGUUCUUUGUGAUACAAAUGAAGAGUAGGGCCUGAGGAUGUUAUUCUUUCUAAUGGAAGGACAUAAAUCUAUUUUAUGUAGUUUUAAAUAGAAUGCCUAAAUUAGGCUGUGGGAGAUAAUUUUUAGUGGUUGUAGGAAAGAGCAAAUUUAGGGAGUGUUGAACUUCAGGCCUUUUAUUCCUGGGAAGAUAUGUAUAGAGAAAACUUUUAAAAUAAUUUUUGAUUAGAAAUAUACAUGUGCCCAUGUAAUAAACAACAGAAUGUGCUCAUUCUGCUAGUGCGGUAUAAUCCGAAUUUGUACUCCCCUAAAAUUUAUCAGAAUAACAAUUAUGCAUACAUGAACUAUGCCAGAGUAAUGUUUACAGAUACUUUGUAACCAAUUUCAGGAGGCGUUUUUAGCUGGAUGUGUAGUUAAUUAGACCAACUUAUUUCCAAAUGGUUUGUUAACAUUUUGCUUUGGUUUACAAUGUCAUGUUGAACACAAAGAAGACCCAGCAGCAAAGGGAUGACCAAUAAUUUCAUCUUAUAGCAAGGAGACAUUCCAACGUUCCCAUGUUUUAUUUUCUGAGAACAGUGGGACAGAUCUGUAGUAAUGGAAUAUUAUUUGCAAAAGGGUUACAUAUGACACAAGUAAGUGUUCUGACAUAAAGUUUUAUUUAGUUCAGUGGCAUGUGCUGUUGGGAGCCAUACACCAUAAAAUAUAUAUAUCCCAAAAUAAAUCUAGAAUAUUUUCACCUCCAAUUUCAGUAAUUGGCAUAUGAUUUGUGAGACGCAUCUGUUUUUGUAUGAGGUUUAAUCACUAGCAAUCUGUUUAAAGAAUCCAGUCCUAUACACAGUUGGACUCAUUCUUGAAACCUUUAAAUGCUCCCUCAUAGUUUUUCAGUUAUUUGGAAGUUGCAUUGGGUCAAACUGAACUCCUUGAGUUUGGUGUAAAUUCCUUUUUUCUGCUUAUUAUAGUGAAACUUCAGCAUGUUUCUUAGUAAACUCCCAUACCAUUGAAAUGCUUAAGCCAGUUGGCUUUCAGUCUCAUGCCUUAUUUCCUCCAAGGCAUGCCUCAACGCAUUGUUUGUCUCAUUGCUUAAAUAUGUCCAGAAGGAAUGAUCAUGUAUCUAAUAGACUACAUAGUUGGUUCCCUUGGGGAGUUAUAUAUCAUACAGUUACUAAAUAUUUGUCUAAAUUCAUUUUUUCCAAAAACCUGCUCUCAAAUUUUUCUUCUACUCUCAGUUCAUAAAUAAUAUAACCAUUGAAACAACACAUCAGCCUCUAGCUGAUCCUCUGAAAGUAGCCAUUGAAAUAAUCGAAUACUGUGUGAACAGGAAAGGAAAGCGUUACCUUUAAGAGAAGCUUUAAAAUAGGAAUUUAUUGAUAUUUCACAAGAUAUAGGUUUACAGAAGACAUUAUUCAAAUAAAUAUGUACACUAUUUGCCUGAUGCUAUGGGGUACAUAAUUUUUUAAAAACUCCCUUAGACCAGCAGCCAUUAGUGUAGAAAUGAUGGACUUUAAAGGUGAUACCAUGUAAGCAGAUGUUGCAUAUAAAAAUAUUCCUGCCUGAAUCUGAUCGAGAUUCUUGAAUGGGGGAGGAGUGGCAGCCGGCAGCACAUUGCAAAUGUCAUUCGAGGUCACGGUGAGGCUCUCGGUCCCGGAACAGUGGGGGCCUCGCCAGGCGUUGCCAGUAUCCCUUUCCUCCUGUAAAAUCAUAGCUUUGUGUUACACGACUGCUUAUCCAGUCUUAGGGUUUAGCAGCUGAAAGGUUUACAAAACUGAAUCUGGUUGAAUCUCUGUGAAAGGGUCAACACAUCUGUCGGCAUUUUGCACACUUAUGUAUUAUUAUGAUACAACAUAUUACUUUAUGGUAAUUUUUAUUUUUACAUAUAACUACCUCCAUAAAUUUGAUGAAAUGGCAGCCGUGUGUUAAAGUGUAUCGUUCAGAAGAGCAAAGUUGAACACUUCCUUCAACAUUAGGGCAUGGCGUGCUGUGUGUGUCAGUGAUUGCCUCUGUGGACUCAUGACUUUCCAUCGCCAUGGCUUUCUCUUACGCCGCUGUUUGGCUUUCAGAUGUAAUCCUGUCUUCUCCUCUCUUCCCCACGAAAGCGCACUCGAUUUUGUUAGGAAUGAACGGAAGUUUAAAAAUUCUUGUGCCCACCCCCGCCCUCCACCCAUUCCUGUUAAAAGUUCUCUGGCGAAGAGCCAAUGGGUGAACGUAAUUGAAAGAGCUAUUUACUCUUUUGGAAAUCUGAUUUGAAGUCUAAGUUUUCAGUAACAGAAGACACACAAGCAAUGUGGACUGCCAAGCUUGAAGCACUUCGGGCUCUGCCUUCACUCGCAUGCUACCAUGUCGAGCCCAAACUCCACUUUAAUUAAAAGAGCUGUGCUGUGAAUUCCACAACUUCUGUUAAAUAAUUUGUAUUCCAUUAUAUAUAUUUUGCACAUCUCAGGGGACCAUAAUGAACAUAUGAAAGGGGGGGGGGUGCCAUCAAAUAGAGAAAACAAAUAGAAGAGGUGAAUGGAGACUAGCUGGAUAAAAAUAACAAAUUACUUCUUCUCUGAUGUUGUGAAGGUCAGGUUCAGGAAGCAUCAAUUCACAGUUAAUCCGGAGUAACAAUGAUCUGAACACCAGCUGUUCCCAGGUCCCUCUUUUUCAUAGCCCAACCAGCAUCUAAAAUGUAAAUUUAAAUUACAUUGCAGUCACCAUGGGGAGAAGAAACCUGUUCAGUGGAAGCAGAAGCAUUGUUCCUUUUUUAGGUUGGCGCAGCUUUGCAAAACUCUACCCAGGAUAAACCACUUAUCACCACCAAGUGUACUUGAAAAUAAAGUUUUUAACUUAAAUUACAAGCAUAUUGCUCAUAAUACAAUAGUGAUCAUUUUUUGAAAGUCUUGCCAUUUAUAACAUGGGCAGUAUUUGGAGCUUCAUUUAAAAACCAACAACAACCGAUAAUGACUUUGCACGAUUCACUUUGGGAUCUCAAAGUGCUUCCAAAGCAUUCAGAUUUACAAACAAUUCACAAGACAGGUCAUCUUUGUAAUACGCAUACUUACAACGAAUUAACAAAAGGAGUGACUUAAGAUUCUCCAGGAACACAGUGGCAGCUAUUGAUGAUCUGUUUUCUAUCUGUUUGAUAGAGCAUCAUGAGAAAUCACAAAAUACAAUGCUAUUUUUCUGAUGUGUGCUAAUAAAGUCAAAGAAAACAAAUACAUCUUGACACUUUUGUCCAUUUUCAUUAAAAAAAAAAAAGUUCAGGGUGUUUGGAAUUUUACAUCUCAGCACACCUUACUGGUAUCAAUGGAUAAAGCGGGUGAUUGACAGAUCCACCCAAAUGCCACUGCAGUCAGAAGCAGAUCUGGACACACCCUUGUUUACAGUUUCAUAUUGGGUUGCUAUAGUUCCCGUGCUAAAUCACCAGCUUUCAGGAACAUGACUGCUCCUGGCAGUGGAAGGUGCUGAAACAGAAAUUUUAAUUAAAAACUUUAUCAAGUACUCUUCACAGUGCUGCUUGGCACCAUAGAAAAUCAGUACAAUAUAUCGAGCCCUACUUUGGAGGAGCUGGAUUUCUGAGGGAGCUGAUCCAGUUCUAAGUGUCUUCUCGAAUUAGGAGAUAGAUGAUCUUUGAUGGGGAUCUCCUCCGUCACCACAGGCCAGUCACAGAACCAACUAGCCACGUGCUGCCAGACCUCAGUGGGCCCAAGCAGGAGCAAUCUCUUCUAUCCCCCAUCUCCCCCAGGACCAUCCCGCCCAUUGUCAACGUCAUCCAGGGCUCUUCUGGUAGUGAGUGACUUUUCUGCACAUGUUUAGGGCUUGGGGGAGCUAGAACACAGGAAACAUGAAUGCAAAAGGCAUGGAAAACACUGUUUUGCUUUGGGUUAGUAAAAUGUGGGCAGGACAAAGAUUACUAUUGGUCUGAGCUUUGCCAAGUGAGAUAGAAUCAACUGUCACCCCAUUCCUUUCCCAGAAGGUCUUAUGGUAUUAAGGAUACAUCCAGUAUUUUCCCACAGAUUUUUAUUCAGGCGAUGUUUCAUAAAUUACAUAUAUGAAAACAUUCAUUAUUACAUUUCCUUGUGUGUUUCAAACAGACAUUGGCACCUUCCUAUUGAGUUAAUUCUCUGCAUCUUUUGCAGCAGCAGCCCACAAGGAGAUUCCCAGAGAUGGCUCCCCUAACACACAGUCCUGUGAUUUUACAGUUCUAUGACUUACAGUUGAUGAUUCACAAGAUUCAGGAUUCUACAAGACUCAAGGGGGAACUAAACUUUCUUACGAUUGUACAUGAUCAGUUAUAGGGCUGUAAUCAUUAAUUGUUGGCUUCAAAUGUGGACACACACACACACACAUCAUGCCAAGGAGGGAAUGGGGUGUUUCAAGUCAGGCAGCGAUGAUUCUGGAAGGUUGGAAAUGUAAGGUUAGAAGCUUGGCUGGUCUUAGUAAACUUGUUCCCUUGCUCCCACCAAGAAGAGGUACCAAAUGUGAGACCUGAGAUCUCCUCCAAUAUCUGUCCUCUGCAGUUCCGGGAAACUAAUCAUGAAGUACACAUGCAGCAGCUCCUCCACUUCCUUUCCUCCGAGGUCCUCCUUUCCAUUCUCCCACCUAGAUACUGACACACCGCCACGGUUUCCACAUUGGAAGGGCAGAACACUGUGCAGUAUCGUGCACACUUGCUGGGUUAGGAAUAGAGCUGCCCUAGGGUCACCUUCAUGCAAGUAUUGACAGCUACAAAUUAAAGUCCUUAGAGCAGUUGACACAGAUACUACGUUCUAGAAGAGAAUUAAAUUUAAACGUCAAGUUUAAAGGGAUCAUAAUUCUGCAGGUAUCUUUCUCUGAGUGACUGAAUGUGACUAUUGCAUUAGGGUAAAUGAAUUAAGACGUGCAAGUGGGAUUUACUGUAUGUUAGAAAGGAGUUUUGCAGCCAAGACUGCCUUGAAUAAAAUGUGUUUGCACUGAAAAAAAAUUUUAAAUUACUUGGUCUCUGGUUGCUGUAAAGGUCAUCCAAGAUGGAUGUUCUGUUUAUAUUGUAUAGUAUUUCAUAUGAAAUAAUUACAGUUCAUGAAAUGUCUUCCCUAAUGUUACUGAUUUAUAACAGCACAUUUGUAACAUGGUUUUUAUCGUGUCAGUGUACCAUACUGUAAAUGAUGAUUACUUGUCAUGCUUAGUAUAAUAACUUAAAAGAAAAAAAAGGACAGGGAUUUUUGUAAGUCUAUAUUUGAAAGUCCCUCCCUAUGGUGAUACUGUGUUCAUGUUGUUUAUGUAGUGUUGUGUGAAAUAUCCAUUUUGGAUUGUGUUACUUUUUAAGAUAUUAAAUAACAUUUGGUUAUA